ACUCACAUGUGGCCACUGCUCACCAUGCACAUAACCCAGCUCAACCGGGAGUGCCUGCUGCACCUCUUCUCCUUCCUAGACAAGGACAGCAGGAAGAGCCUUGCCAGGACCUGCUCCCAGCUCCACGACGUGUUUGAGGACCCCGCACUCUGGUCCCUGCUGCACUUCCGUUCCCUCACUGAACUCCAGAAGGACAACUUCCUCCUGGGCCCGGCACUCCGCAGCCUCUCCAUCUGCUGGCACUCCAGCCGCGUGCAGGUGUGCAGCAUUGAGGACUGGCUCAAGAGUGCCUUCCAGAGAAGCAUCUGCAGCCGGCACGAGAGCCUGGUCAAUGAUUUCCUCCUCCGGGUGUGCGACAGGGUAAGAGGAUUAAAUGACACAGUGGCACCUGGCACAUAGUAGGCUUUCUGCUGUGCGCUCCCCACGGAGGCGGGAGGCGCCUGCACCGUCCUCGGGGACUCCGAUCGCCGUUGGACCGAAAUCACCUCGGUGGGGAGGACCUGACCACUCGGAGUUCGCCGACUUGCGCUCGGGGGUGACGGGGGCCAGGGCUGCCGCGCGCAGGGGUCUGGGGAGCCUCCGGGCGGAGCGACCCAGCGAGACCCCGCCGGCUCCCGGAGUGUCCUGGGGACCGCCACCUCCAGGAGCCCCGGUGGUGAUCUCGGUGAAGCAGGAGGAGGGGAAGCAGGGGCGCACGGGCAGAAGGAGCCACCGAGCCGCUCCUCCUUGCGGUUUUGCCCGCACGCGCGUCUGCCCGCCCACCUUUCCUGGGGCGGAUGCGUUCCCGCAGUGACCGCACUCGCGAUUGUAGAAAAUUCGCUCCCAAUUGUUGAAUGCUUACAUAAACUGCAUAGUUACCCAUAUUUUCUACUGUUCUCAUAAGGGAAAAAGAAAUGAUUUGGAAGAAAAAAAAAGCCUCAAACUAAACAAAAACAAAACCAGCAGCCCUGGCUAAGCUUUUGAUAAUGGAACCAUUAUAAGCUGACAAGCUAGAUUUUUCACCUGUUGGAUUUGCUGGACAUGAGCACAAGCCUAGGCUUCCAAUUUGAAUUUCAGGGCUGUAGUCACUGAUGUGUCACAUUUAGUGAAGGCUCUCGGCCCCCCGGCAGCCGCCUGGUCCUGGGUCACUGGGGAGAAUUCUGGGUGGGUGGAAGAGGCGAGGAGCACUGUGAUGGGCGCUGUUCACACUCCGGCUCCACCCAGCGCCAGCUGCGACAAAGCCCUUUACCCCUCCCAGGCCAGGUGUUUCUUCUGUGUGAAAGAGGAGCUUGAUCCCUACUCACAGGUUCCUUAAUUCAUUGCUCAAAUAGGGAAACGGCAAGGAAAAAGACAAAUUCUGUUCUCAUGAAGCUUACCUUCUAGUGGGGGAAGAGACAACAGGUAACUGGUAUAUAAGAGGGUAGAAGGGCCAGGUGCGGUGGCUCAAUGCCUGUAAUCCCAGCACUUUAGGAGGCCAAGAUGGGCGAUUCACGAGGUCAGGAGAUCGAGACCAUCCUGGCUAACAAGGUGAAACCCCCGUCUGUACUAAAAAAAAAUACAAAAAAUUAGCCGGGCGUGGUGGCGGGCACCUGUAGUCCCAGCUACUCAGGAGGCUGAGGCAGGAGAAUGGCGUGAACCCGGGAGGCGGAGCUUGCAGUGAGCCAAGAUCGUGCCACUGCACUCCAGCCUGGGCGACAGAGAGACUCUUGUCUCAAAAAAAAAAAAAAAAAAAAAAAAAUGGUAGAAAGUAUUUGGAAAAAAGUGCAGGCUGUAACAAGGGCUAUUAGGGAUUGCUGGCAAGAGAUUGGGGGGUGAAGCCUCUGAGAAAGGGUUGACCAAUGUAAGCCUCACUGAGAAGAUGACAUCUGAGGCAUGAAGUGAGGCAGGGGGCAUAGAUACUCCUGGCAGAGGAACAGUCAGUGCAGAGGCCGCGGACUACAGGCAUGGCUCAUGUGCAAGGAGAUCAGAGUGGCUGGAGCAGAGUGAAUGAGGAGGGAAGCUGAGUAGCAGGUAUCUGAGAAGCAAUGCAGCCCGCAGCUUAACUUCAACAUGCUUUUAAACUUUUUUCCCAUUCUCUUGAGUUUCAAGAUAUAACCUUGAGGAAACUCAAAAUCCUUUCUCCUUAGCCUUAAAAUAGACUCCACGUCCCUCCCCUUUCUCACCAGAUAUGCUCCCUUUUCAUUUAUCUAACUGUAUGCUACUAUUUAAUUGUGUGAUGUCUUAGAAGUUUCAGUGGCUAAUCUUGAGACAGACCAAGCCUGGAGACCCAGCUGCAAACCUCCAAAAAUUACUUCAAAAUGGCUAAUUAACAACCUGACCAUUGUUAAAAUAAUGUCAAUCCGAGGUCCAGGUGGACUGAAGCCCAAGAUAGCCACCAGAACAAAACACACAGACAUCAUACUCAGCCCAUUUCUUGCAUGCCUUCCUUAUCAAGUCUUCCCUUUUAAAAACCCUAAAAAUUGCUUUCCCCUCUAAAAAUUGAAGCAGUUACUUUAAAUAGCAAUCUGGCUACUUCCCCCUUUACUAGUUUUGGGUAAUAAAUUUGCUUUUUAUUACUAGA